AGAGCGUGUUGUUAGAGCUGUGCUGAGCGGGUGUUUGGGUUGUUGGCUGCUUUCUUCCCCCUUUCUCACACACUUGUAUAUUAUUUUGAGGUGGUGUUCGCAGAGUUUGAAAGGAGAGAGAAUUAAAAAAAAAAGCCGCAAGCGUUUCACUCUUUUAUUUUUAUAAUCCCCUUCAAUUUGGGGUUAAAAAAAAGACAAGAAAACAGGAAGGAAGAGAAAUAAGGAAAUGAGAUGUGGUAAAAGAAGCUAAAAGGUGCCUUUUAAAAGAUCGUUGCUGUGAAGUGAAAAAAAUCUCCAGAGAAACCAAAAAGCACCGCCGAGACCUCUUCCGAACCAAAGGAGUUUGUGUUUGCUUUUAGGGAAGAAGAAAGAUCAUUCAUUCGGAGGAAUAACAACCAAUUAAAAGACAAAUAAAAAAAGUUUGGAGUGGGACGCAGAGCGAGCGAGAGGAGCUGCCGGCGGGCGGUGGGGCGCGGAGCCCGCACUUUCCCGGCCGGGUGAGCGGCGGCCGCGGCGCCGGGCUCGGCGGGUGCGCCUCGGCGGAGCGAACGUCGGAGCGUUGCCUUGGGAGACGCGCGCCGGACAAUGCCCGCGGCGGGCCAGUGACGCCCGCGGGGAAUGCGGAGCGGCCCGGCAGCCGGCACCCAGCCGCCGCCGCGCGUUCCUGCCGCCCGUGUCACGCGAGACCCGGCGGGGGCCGGGACCGCCCGAGCCGCCCCUCAGACCGAGCCGGCCGCCUCCGCUGCCGCGGCCGCCUCCUCUUCGGGGUCAUUAAAGCCAAUGAGCCGCGCGCCUCUGCCGAGCGCAGCCAACUAAAUCGGCUUGGAUGAUUCGCGACCUGAGCAAGAUGUACCCGCAGACCAGACACCCAGCACCGCAUCAGCCUGCUCAACCCUUUAAAUUUACAAUUUCCGAAUCCUGUGAUCGGAUUAAGGAAGAGUUUCAGUUUUUACAGGCUCAAUACCACAGUCUGAAGCUGGAAUGUGAGAAACUCGCCAGUGAGAAGACAGAGAUGCAGCGGCAUUAUGUCAUGUAUUAUGAAAUGUCCUAUGGGUUGAAUAUAGAAAUGCACAAGCAGGCAGAGAUUGUCAAGAGGCUGAAUGCUAUCUGUGCACAAGUCAUUCCUUUCCUGUCCCAAGAGCACCAGCAACAAGUGGUGCAGGCUGUGGAACGGGCCAAGCAGGUGACCAUGGCAGAACUGAACGCCAUCAUUGGGGAGAAAAAGAAUAAAAGUGACACACCUGGAUCAUUAAAGUCAAACAUAGGAAGACAUGUGGGAGUGGAAGAAAAUAAACCUAAUUUGGAGAGGAGAAAAAAAGGUCCACUUUUUUUCUCUGAGCAGCAACAACUCCAGGCCCAGCAUUUAUCACAUGGACAUGGUCUCCCCGUACCUCUGACUCCACACCCUUCAGGGCUCCAGCCCCCUGCCAUUCCACCCAUCGGUAGCAGUGCCGGGCUUCUGGCCCUCUCCAGUGCUCUAGGAGGUCAGUCCCAUCUUCCAAUUAAAGAUGAGAAGAAGCACCAUGACAAUGAUCACCAAAGAGACAGAGACUCCAUCAAGAGCUCUUCAGUAUCCCCAUCAGCCAGUUUCCGAGGUGCUGAGAAGCACAGAAACUCCGCAGACUACUCCUCAGAGAGCAAAAAGCAGAAAACUGAAGAAAAGGAAAUUGCAGCUCGUUAUGACAGCGAUGGUGAGAAAAGUGAUGACAACUUGGUGGUUGACGUUUCCAAUGAGGAUCCAUCUUCCCCUCGAGGGAGCCCAGCACAUUCCCCCAGAGAGAAUGGCCUAGACAAGACACGCCUGCUCAAGAAAGAUGCCCCGAUUAGUCCAGCCUCUAUUGCAUCUUCCAGCAGUACUCCCUCCUCCAAAUCCAAAGAACUUAGCCUUAAGAGGGAUAUGGGGAAAUUGAGUGAAACACGUCUUAGCGAAGAUGAACAAUGCACAUUGGGGUUACAGAGAUGGUUUUGUCGCCUGUGGUUUAUGAAUGAAAAAUCUACUACUCCCGUCUCAAAGUCCAAUACCCCUACUCCACGAACUGAUGCGCCCACCCCAGGCAGUAACUCUACUCCCGGAUUGAGGCCUGUACCUGGAAAACCACCAGGAGUUGACCCUUUGGCCUCAAGCCUAAGGACCCCAAUGGCAGUACCUUGUCCAUAUCCAACUCCAUUUGGGAUUGUGCCCCAUGCUGGAAUGAACGGAGAGCUGACCAGCCCCGGAGCGGCCUACGCUGGGCUCCACAACAUCUCCCCUCAGAUGAGCGCAGCUGCUGCCGCCGCCGCUGCUGCUGCUGCCUAUGGGAGAUCACCAGUGGUGGGAUUUGAUCCACACCAUCACAUGCGUGUGCCAGCAAUACCUCCAAACCUGACAGGCAUUCCAGGAGGAAAACCGACCAAAUGCUUUUACCACCUGAGGGCUUUCCCUGGAAAUGAACUGGAGAUGGAACUGCCAAGAGAUACUCACAGAGCAUACUCCUUCCAUGUUAGCGCAGAUGGUCAGAUGCAGCCUGUCCCUUUUCCACCCGACGCCCUCAUCGGACCUGGAAUCCCCCGGCAUGCUCGCCAGAUCAACACCCUCAACCACGGGGAGGUGGUGUGCGCGGUGACCAUCAGCAACCCCACGAGACACGUGUACACGGGUGGGAAGGGCUGCGUCAAGGUCUGGGACAUCAGCCACCCAGGCAAUAAGAGUCCUGUCUCCCAGCUCGACUGUCUGAACAGGGAUAACUACAUCCGUUCCUGCAGAUUGCUCCCUGAUGGUCGCACCCUAAUUGUUGGAGGGGAAGCCAGUACUUUGUCCAUUUGGGACCUGGCGGCUCCAACCCCACGCAUCAAGGCAGAGCUGACAUCCUCGGCCCCCGCCUGCUAUGCCCUGGCCAUCAGCCCCGAUUCCAAGGUCUGCUUCUCAUGCUGCAGCGACGGCAACAUCGCUGUGUGGGAUCUGCACAACCAGACCUUGGUGAGGCAAUUCCAGGGCCACACAGAUGGAGCCAGCUGUAUUGACAUUUCUAAUGAUGGCACCAAGCUCUGGACAGGUGGUUUGGACAACACGGUCAGGUCCUGGGACCUGCGCGAGGGGCGGCAGCUGCAGCAGCACGACUUCACCUCCCAGAUCUUUUCUCUGGGCUACUGCCCAACUGGAGAGUGGCUUGCAGUGGGGAUGGAGAACAGCAAUGUGGAAGUUUUGCAUGUCACCAAGCCAGACAAAUACCAACUACAUCUUCAUGAGAGCUGUGUGCUGUCGCUCAAGUUUGCCCAUUGUGGCAAAUGGUUUGUAAGCACUGGAAAGGACAACCUUCUGAAUGCCUGGAGAACACCUUAUGGGGCCAGUAUAUUCCAGUCCAAAGAAUCCUCAUCGGUGCUUAGCUGUGACAUCUCCGUGGACGACAAAUACAUUGUCACUGGCUCUGGGGAUAAGAAGGCCACAGUUUAUGAAGUUAUUUAUUAAAGACAAAUCUUCAUGCAGACUGGACUUCUCCUCCUGGUAGCACUUUGCUCUGUCAUCCUUUUUGUUCACCCCCAUCCCCGCAUCUAAAACCAAGGAUUUCAGAUACUCAUUGCAGUUGUGGAGUUUAAUCCCCUUUCUUAACCUCACUUCCCACUUGCUAUUGAAUUGUGAAUAGUCAUUAAAAACCUGUGAUACCAAAUCUUCAGCUGUCUACUUGGAAGAACAUGGAAUAAGCAUACUUAACAGUGAAAAGAAUCUUUAAUUAUGUAUUAUAUCUGUAAUAUAUUUAUUUUGUUUAAAGAAGGCUUUCUAACAAUGACUGACUAAAUAAAGCUGUCUGCUCCUGCAUUGAUAAUGAAGGUGCGUUGUAUUUGAUACCCCUCCCCCCCUUUUUUUGGCAAAGGAGGGGAAAGGAAGGUUUAAAAUAAUUGAUUUAAAAUGUCACUAAGUGUAGACUGAUGACUGUAUAGAGAUGUGAAAUGUAUAAUUACACAUGGAAGCAAUAUGUUGCUGUGUUGUUAUUAGGUUUUUUUUGUUUUUGUUUUCUACAUCUUUUAAAGACUUUUGGAAAUUUGGCUGAACAAUUAGAACACAACAGGCCAACUCAUACUCAUUUGGAUCUAUUUAGACAACGUUAACCAAUAUAUCUAUAGCUUUAGAUUAUAUUCGAUAAAAGUAAUUGGACUUUUUUUCUUUUUUUGACUCGUUGACAAGUGUCUUUGUAAUAUGUUUUUAGUUCCCUUUUUUUGUUGUAUUAUAGGCAGAUGAACAAAUUAAAUUUGGCCUCAAAGAGAGAACUUACUCCCUUCUGGAUAUUUUUGCCACAUUUCUUUGCAAAAGGAGAUAUAUAUAUCUUUAGUCAGUUUUGUUGUUAUGAGAAAUUAUGGGUUAUUUUGUGGCAUGCUCUUUGGGAGCUGCACAGUUAUGGGGAGGACUCCCACUGCUGUGCAAGUUAAGUCUUUUACAAAACAAGGACAGCAGAGGAGGGUUUGCAGAGACCUCCCUCUGAAAAACACAAAGAAUGGACUCUCUCCUGGGAUGAGGACUUGCUUUCUUUACCUCCGGUUCUUUCCAUGUCUUAGUUGGAUGUCCCUGAAAUGGACACAGGCUGUGCCAUUGUGCCAGAAACAUUGUGUUAUCUUUUAUGUUGUUGUUGUUGCUGUUAAACUAUAAUAUGUGACUUCUUUUUUUAUUAUUUUUUGUUUGAAUGCUUUAAAAAUCUUUUAAGUCUGUGGAUCUGCUGAUGUACAGUGCCUUUGCUGCUAUGGAUCAAAAUCAAAAGAACCGUGUAGAUAUACUUUAUUGUAUAAGUAGAAAAUUACUUAAUUUCAUACUAGAAAUGGAUGGAUGCUGCAAGUUGAAAUGGACUGUCCAUUGACGUUCCUAAUGUGGUAGCAGAAAAAAAAAAAUGGUGUCUUAAGUGCUUAGUGUUUGAUGUCAUUAACAGUUUCGUAAAACUCUACAGUGUAGAAAGAUUUUGAUACUAAACUGUGCGUUGUACAUAGUUCUAAUGCAUUGUAUUGACCACCAGUACUUCUAUAAUGGUAGAUUGUUUGUGAAUUCAGACUUUUAAGCAUUAAACAUAAAUAACUUCUAGUAUGCUUAUUUUUCUAAUUCUUUGUCUUGAUGACAUUAGUUUAUUUUUUAUCUUUGGCUGUGCCACUCCUAUAUAUUAAAAAUGCCUAGUUUUUUCAAGGGAGAUUGUUGUUAAAGUAAAGUGGUUUUUUUUGUUGUUAAA